GGUAAUUGCCAAGGAGAGAGCAGCACGUAGAUCCUCCCUGUCAUCAGGCAGAGCUCUUCAGUGAGGUGGGCUCAGGGAGGGCUCUGUGCCUCCGUUCAGCAGAGCUGCAGCUGCUGCCCAGCUCUCAGGAGGCAAGCUGGACUCCCUCACUCAGCUGCAGGAGCAAGGACAGUGAGGCUCAACCCCGCCUGAGCCAUGCCAGCCAACUUCACAGAGGGCAGCUUCGAUUCCAGUGGGACCGGGCAGACGCUGGAUUCUUCCCCAGUGGCUUGCACUGAAACAGUGACUUUUACUGAAGUGGUGGAAGGAAAGGAAUGGGGUUCCUUCUACUACUCCUUUAAGACUGAGCAAUUGAUAACUCUGUGGGUCCUCUUUGUUUUUACCAUUGUUGGAAACUCCGUUGUGCUUUUUUCCACAUGGAGGAGAAAGAAGAAGUCAAGAAUGACCUUCUUUGUGACUCAGCUGGCCAUCACAGAUUCUUUCACAGGACUGGUCAACAUCUUGACAGAUAUUAAUUGGCGAUUCACUGGAGACUUCACGGCACCUGACCUGGUUUGCCGAGUGGUCCGCUAUUUGCAGGUUGUGCUGCUCUACGCCUCUACCUACGUCCUGGUGUCCCUCAGCAUAGACAGAUACCAUGCCAUCGUCUACCCCAUGAAGUUCCUUCAAGGAGAAAAGCAAGCCAGGGUCCUCAUUGUGAUCGCCUGGAGCCUGUCUUUUCUGUUCUCCAUUCCCACCCUGAUCAUAUUUGGGAAGAGGACACUGUCCAACGGUGAAGUGCAGUGCUGGGCCCUGUGGCCUGACGACUCCUACUGGACCCCAUACAUGACCAUCGUGGCCUUCCUGGUGUACUUCAUCCCUCUGACAAUCAUCAGCAUCAUGUAUGGCAUUGUGAUCCGAACUAUUUGGAUUAAAAGCAAAACCUACGAAACAGUGAUUUCCAACUGCUCAGAUGGGAAACUGUGCAGCAGCUAUAACCGAGGACUCAUCUCAAAGGCAAAAAUCAAGGCUAUCAAGUAUAGCAUCAUCAUCAUUCUUGCCUUCAUCUGCUGUUGGAGUCCAUACUUCCUGUUUGACAUUUUGGACAAUUUCAACCUCCUUCCAGACACCCAGGAGCGUUUCUAUGCCUCUGUGAUCAUUCAGAACCUGCCAGCAUUGAAUAGUGCCAUCAACCCCCUCAUCUACUGUGUCUUCAGCAGCUCCAUCUCUUUCCCCUGCAGGGCUAAUAGCAGUGUCUACCUGUUGGCCUGUGAUGUCUCUGUCCUCUGGGCUCUGGUGCUGACCAGUGAGAAGGAGAGCUGUGAGUCAUGGAGAAGGAAGGGAGCAAAGAUCACAGGAUUCCAGAAUGACGUUCCGGGAGAGAACUGAGAGGCAUGAGAUGCAGAUUCUGUCCAAGCCAGAAUUCAUCUAGACCCUAGGGCAGUGCCAGUGCUAGGCUGAGCACCAUCAGCUCUCCCAGGUCCUUGUCACCUGCUUGGGCACGUGCAUGGAACCCGAGCCAACUUCACCCCACCCUCGUCAUUACCUGGGAGAUGCACAAGACAAAUGUUCUAAUGACUGCAUGCACUGCUUAAGUAUUGGCCAACACGAACUCCCCAGUUAUUCAUGCCAGCCAGGAAGGAAACGCCUUCCUUCCCCACCAUUCCCAGCCCUCCUUCCCACUGGCCAGCACCUGAACCCAGUGAACACAGGCAUUAGUGGUCCAGGGUCCUGGCUUGGAGCCAGUGAGUAGAC